GUGGAAGGCCGGCGUGCGAGCCGUGAGGGGUGUGCGCGCGUGAGCCGGAGCGGGGCUCGCCCCUCGCCGGCGCCCGCCGCCCAGCCGGUGAUUGCUCUCUGGCUGUCCCCGGCACCUCGGCCCCCACGGCCGUUGGUCCGGGCGGGUGAGGGAGAAAGUGAGACUUGGUGUCAUCACCAUCCAUUGUCAGAAGGGGAGGAAAUUGGAAUCCAGCAGCGGCGAGCAGCAGCUGGGCGGUCACAUCUGGGAAUGCAAAGCCGACCUCCCCCUCCUCCUCCUCCUCCCCCUCCUCCUCCUCCUCUUCUCUCACCCAGGAUCACUUCCGAAACCACUUCGCCUUCAGCCCCUGCCUCGGCCAGAGGUUUCAUUUUUAACUGAAUAUUUACGAAAGCUGGAAGCGUGCGAGGGGGGUGGGGUGGGGUGGAAAUAGCGGCUGCUUCUUUUCCAGGGAUUUAUUUAAUGGGGAUGUGUUCAAGGCAAGAGCGAAUUCAGAAGGAUAUCGACGUCGUGAUCCAGAAGUCCAGAGCUGAGAAGGACUGCCUGUUUGCAGAUUUCAGAUACUCUGACUCCACCUUUACUUUUACCUACGUUGGCGGCCCCAGAAGGAAUUCAGAGCUUGCUCCAGGGAUGUGAGGACAAAAGAUGAGUAUGACUUUUAAAAGGAAUUCAGAACUUGCUCUAGAUUUUGCUUUCUUCUCAUGUCCACCUUCUUUCACUUUCACUUAUGCUUCUUGACAAUAUUUUCUGCCUGCUACAUGGCAUUUAUUAUGUACAGCACAUACUAACAGUACUCUGCAAUCUACUUAAGCUUUGUUCUUUCCACGUUUUUUUGGUACUACUCAUUAGAUCCUUGAGCCAAUCAUCCAUGUCUGUUUGUACUAGAUUGUUUCCCUUAGAACUCUGCAAGUCACAAAGUGAAACUGAUUAGGAUUUUACAGUCCUGGUGAUUUUCCUUCUGGUAUACCACUGAGAAAAUGCUGUCGCACAAGGGGCUGAUGAAUCAUUUUGCAGGAUUUCUGUUUGCUAUUUUCUAUUUGAAAAAUUAGUGUAUCCUACUCAGUACAUGUAUCUGAAGAUUACCCAGCUAUUGUGAAUACUGCCACAAUGCACAUGGUGGUGGAGAUAUUGCUUCAAGAUCCUGGUUCCGUUUCCUGUGGAUCUCAAAAGGAUUGCUGAAAUGGAUAAUACAUAUGUGUCAAGUUCAGAGAAUGAUGAAGAUGUGCUAGUUACUACAGAGCCAAUACCAGUAAUUUUUCAUAGAAUAGCAACAGAAUUAAGAAAAACAAAUGACAUUAACUGUUGCUUAUCCAUAAAAUCCAAAUUACAAAAGGAAAAUGGGGAGGAAUCAAGACAGAAUAGUACAGUGGAGGAAGAUUCUGAAGGUGACAAUGAUUCCGAAGAAUUUUAUUACGGAGGGCAGGUGAACUAUGAUGGGGAACUGCACAAGCACCCACAACUGGAAGCUGAUUUGUCAGCAGUUAGAGAGAUAUAUGGGCCACAUGCAGUUUCUCUCAGGGAAUAUGGAGCCAUUGAUGAUGUAGAUAUUGAUCUGCAUAUCGAUGUUAGCUUUCUUGAUGAGGAGAUUGCUGUGGCUUGGGAAGUAAUUCGAACAGAACCUAUAAUUGUUCGACUACACUGUUCACUUACACAGUAUUUAAAUGGCCCAGUGCCCACUGUUGAUGUCUUUCAGAUUUCCACAAAAGAGCGAUUUGGAUUGGGACAUCAGCUGAAAAAAAUCAUGCAGACAUUUGUUACACAGCAGUGGAAACAGAGCAAAGAAAAAUCCAAUUGCCUGCACAAUAAAAAGUUGUCAGAGAAGAAAGUGAAGUCUCCCCUGCAUUUAUUUUCUACUUUGCGCAGGUCGCCAAGUUAUCCUCCCCCUGGUUGUGGCAAAAGCAAAUCCAAACUGAAAUCUGAGCAGGACGGAAUCUCCAAAACGCAUAAGCUGCUGCGGAGGACUUGUUCCAGCACAGUCAAGACUGAUGAUGUGUGUGUCACAAAGUCACACAGGACCUUUGGCCGCUCCUUGUCCAGCGAUCCCAGGGCGGAGCAGGCUAUGACAGCAAUUAAAUCGCACAAACUUUUGAACCGUCCUUGCCCUGCAGCUGUUAAGUCAGAGGAAUGCCUAACUCUAAAGUCGCAUAGACUAUUGACUCGAUCUUGUUCUGGAGAUCCACGAUGUGAGCACAACACAAACUUGAAGCCCCAUAAACUGUUAAGCAGGUCUUACUCUAGUAAUCUCAGAAUGGAAGAAUUAUAUGGACUGAAAAAUCACAAAUUGCUCAGCAAGUCCUACUCCAGUGCCCCCAAGUCAUCCAAAACUGAGCUUUUCAAGGAACCUAACGCAGAGGGCAGGAGGCUCUCUCUUACCUCAGGGCUUAUUGGUAUCCUAACACCAUCUUCAUCUUCAUCUUCUCAGCUUGCUCCAAAUGGUGCAAAAUGCAUUCCAGUACGAGACCGUGGCUUCCUGGUGCAGACAAUUGAGUUUGCUGAACAGCGGAUCCCUGUAUUAAAUGAAUAUUGUGUGGUUUGUGAUGAGCCACAUGUGUUUCAAAAUGGCCCUAUGCUUAGGCCUACCGUAUGUGAACGGGAGCUGUGUGUGUUUGCUUUUCAAACCCUGGGAGUAAUGAAUGAAGCUGCUGAUGAAAUAGCAACUGGAGCUCAGGUGGUAGAUCUACUAGUAUCCAUGUGUAGGUCUGCGUUGGAAUCUCCUAGAAAAGUUGUGAUUUUCGAGCCAUAUCCUUCUGUGGUAGAUCCUAAUGAUCCUCAGAUGUUGGCCUUCAACCCCAGGAAAAAGAACUAUGAUCGAGUAAUGAAAGCACUGGAUAGCAUAACUUCUAUCAGAGAAAUGACACAAGCACCAUAUCUGGAAAUCAAGAAGCAAAUGGAUAAACAGGACCCCCUUGCUCAUCCCUUACUGCAAUGGGUUAUAUCAAGUAAUAGAUCACAUAUUGUGAAACUGCCAGUUAACAGGCAAUUGAAGUUUAUGCAUACUCCACAUCAGUUCCUUCUUCUCAGCAGUCCACCAGCCAAAGAAUCCAAUUUUAGAGCUGCUAAAAAACUCUUUGGAAGCACCUUUGCAUUUCAUGGCUCACACAUUGAAAACUGGCACUCCAUCCUGAGGAAUGGUCUGGUUGUUGCUUCUAAUACACGAUUGCAGCUCCAUGGUGCAAUGUAUGGAAGUGGAAUCUAUCUUAGUCCAAUGUCAAGCAUAUCAUUUGGUUACUCAGGGAUGAACAAGAAACAGAAGGUGUCAGCCAAGGACGAGCCAGCUUCAAGCAGUAAAAGCAGCAAUACAUCACAGUCACAGAAAAAAGGACAGCAAUCCCAAUUCCUGCAAAGCCGUAACUUAAAAUGCAUAGCCUUAUGUGAAGUGAUCACCUCAUCUGACCUGCACAAACAUGGAGAGAUAUGGGUUGUCCCCAAUACUGACCAUGUCUGCACACGAUUCUUUUUCGUCUAUGAAGACGGCCAAGUGGGAGAUGCAAAUAUUAAUACACAAGAAGGAGGCAUUCACAAAGAGAUCCUCCGAGUAAUUGGUAAUCAAACUGCUACUGGUUAAAGGACCACCAUUUAAUUAACAUGAUUCGAAAGCCUUCCUCGGGUUCAAAGCUGGAUUUUGAACUGAAGAAGAUUAUAAAAUUAUUUAUUGUUAUUAUAAACAAAAUUAACCCUUUGAAUACUGAUUUUUUUUCUUAGUAUUUCUAAGUAUCUCAUUAAAUACCUAAAAUGGUAUAAGAUUUAUCAAUUGUAGGGUUAUGGAAUCUAGUAAUAAAAUUUCAACAGCACUUAAACUGAAGUUUGGGUUGCUCAUACAAUAAACAGAUUGAAAAAACUGUUUUGUGCUGAUAUUUUUAUACUAAACUCUUUAACUGGAUAUUUGGUAUUAUAUACCGACAUUUUAGGUUACCAAAAUAGAAUUGAGAACAUUUUAUAAUGGCAUCUAAAUCUAUCAGAUACUUUGCAAUAAGUAUACUGUUUGCACAUUCUGAUGUGCUAUAUCAUUAGUAGUAUGGGCAUUCUAAUGUUUUGGAAGGGGUGUUCCCUAUUCUAUUUUUCUUCAUAAAAAAAGAAGUAGGUCUUAGAAGCAGUGCUUUGCCAAAAAGUAUGUAAUAUACACAUCUAUACAUUCAUGCAUCAAAAUGUGUGGUUGUGAAUAUAUUUGUGUAUAUUCACACGUAUGUUUUGACAAGAAAGAUGGCUUAGCUUCACAAUUCUAUCCUCGUUUAAUGGAAAGAAGAUAAUAUUUAGUAAGCAAUAAAUUUGGACAUAAAUCAAGAUAUGAGCCAGAUUUACCACCAUUCAUUCACUGAAAAUAUUUGCAGACAAUUUUUCUGUUUGUCUGAAGAAAUUCAGCCCUUUUAAAAUGUUAUCUAAAAGUCAUAAUUUGGGGAACAUACAUGGCCUGGUAGACCGAAUCUAUAUUCAAAUGAUUAUGUAUUUAAAAGAAAGACCUCAGAAUUUAAAGAAACCAUAUAUAUUUUUUAUUUACUACAAAAAAAUUAUACAAUUUUAUUUAUGCCACACCAGCAUUUUUAUAUUUGUUCAUCUAAUAUCUCUGCUUAUUUUUUUCAUAUUGAGAAAGAACACAAACUUGAUGCUUCUUUUAUAUUAAAAGACCACAAAUAAGUUUAUAGAGAACAGUAACACCAGCUCUCAGCAUUUCCUUUUCAAGAGUCAUAAUUUCAUCAAAAUCAUUUCUUAUUCUUUGAGUCCUAGAGUUCUUAUUCAUCAAGUUUUAAUUGACAGUGUUUAUUUUCCCACAUGUUGUCUUUGGAAUAAGGCCAUUCAUGAAAGCAGUUUAAUUAGUGAGUCUGCCACUCUAUUCAAACCCUGAAUCAAGGCUCUAUCUGAUUUUAAUUUAUGUAAAAAAAAAUAAAAAUGUAUAGUCAUUUGCAAGUAUAAUGUGAUAACUGCUGUGUUUAUUUCCUUUGUCUGGCAUAAAAGGUGAGAAAAAGGUCAUACAUGUUGUUAAGGGUAGCAGUUUAGGAAGUGUUUUCUAAUAAUUUGUUUUGUUAUAUUGCAAAUAAUUGAUAUGCCACUUAUUUCUGCAAGAAAAAUAGGCUUGAAGUGGUUGGGAUAUUAAUCAUUUUGAUAGUAUCUACUUAAAGCAUUGAUCUGUUUUGACUUGUGGCUCUGAACCCUGGGCUAGGCUGAGGGAUAAUAGUAGUGGAGUAGGGCAAAGAUAUAAUAUCCUAUCCAGUGUUUUGUGACCACUUAUUUGAAGAUUAGUGUGGGACAUGAGGACCUUGCUACUUUUUUGCCAAGAUGCUGCAAGUCUCCCAAAUCACUUCAACUGUGUUUUUAAAACAUGUUUAAGCAACAGAAUUAUUUUUUUGAAAUUAGUCUAUACGUUAGACAGUCUAUACAUGACAAACAUGAAGAUCUAAUAUCAAGAUUUGGGAGACGGGAUCUUGGAACUCCACCUGUUUGACCACUAGGACCACUGAGGCACCUCCAAUAAGCUCUGUAGAGUGCCUCCAGCAUAAUUCAAAAUCCACUGACCUAAUCCAUUAUGGCUUUACUUAACAUUGGAGUGAUCCGUAAAGAAUAUAGUAUUGGAGUCUGAACUGGAACGGUAACUCGUAAGACUCAAGAAAGACCGUUUAAGGAAAAUUGGCAUAAUACAAACUGUUCCUGUUGACUUAAGAAUAACAGUAGGUUCACCUAUCUGAGGAAAUUAAGUAGUUGAUAGUUUAAUGCUAGGCAUCUUUUAUGAUAAUAAAGUAAGAUGUCUUCUUAUGACAGUUAAUUGAGUUGUAUCAUGAUACAGAAUGACAGAUUUUGUUUCAAACAAUUGCGUCAGAACCUUUGUAAGCAAAUAUUCUAAGGAGAAUCAAUCUUAUUUUUUAAUUGAACUUUUUGAAAUUAGGGAUACUAUAAUAACUGAUAAAGAUGAAUUUCUGUGUUUCUAAAGAAUCUAAUUUCAAUUACUACCAUUAACAUAUAAAUGUGCUUCCAAAAUCCAAGCAGGUCCAUACAAUUUAGAGAUUUGAACACUGUUAUCAUGCUUUAAUUCAGUCAUUCAUUAAAAUAUUAUCUAUUCACUUAUUUGAUGAUUCCAAACAUUUGAUAUUGUAUUGUGUUUUUAUAAUUAUUUGAAAUCUGUUCACCAAUGCUUUGUAAUGGUUUUAUUAAUUGUGUAGCCAUUGCUACUUAGAUAGUAACCCACUGAGCAAAGGCAGUCAUUUAUUUUCAUCCUUGAAGUAGGGGAAGAAAAUUAUUAAUUUAUUAGUUCUACUUUUUCCUGCAUUGCUUAUUUUGUAAACAUUUUACUAUGAAUAAUCUGUUCUCUUUCACUGUAUUAAAAGGAGAAGAAAAUGAACAUUUGAGAAUGGAAAAAAGUAAUAAUAUACAAAUAAUCUAGUGCUAUAAAAUGCAUUAUAGUAAGACACUUUUGGUGUCUUCGAGUGCACUAUGUUGGAAUAAAUUUUAUACUUGUUGCUUAGUAAAUCUCAGUCAUACGUUUGGUUUGAAGCUGUUUUUUUUUUUAAUUUGAAGUUUAAUUUUAAAAGUGCCACAUUGUAAAAGUUACCGUUAAAUACUAUGUAGUAUAAAAAACCAACCCAAGCUAUUGUUAAUGCUCUGAAUGUUUUUCUUUGAAAAUUUAAGUUUAGAGAAGAAAUUCCUUCAUUUUUCUCCCCUUUGCUAAAAGAAAGAAAAUCUAUAAUAUGUAAGUCUAUGAAUCUUUAAAUAACUGAAGGAAUUUUAGCAGUACUUUGUAUAAUAAAAAUAUUUUUUAAACUAUAACUUGCCUUAGAGCAUGGGGUUUCAGAAAGUUUUGACGAAAAACUCAUCUUCAUUAAAGAGUCUGGAUAACUUCAUCAGAUGGUAAUUUAAUAUGUCAUGAAGGGGACACUCAACAUUGGGUCAUCUACCGUCUAAAUAAAUACGGAUUUCAUGGUGGCAUUUGAAGCACAUUUUGCAAACAUUAUGAUGUUCUAUUGUCUUGCUGAAUUCUUUAUUAUAACACUACCUCAAGACAAAUGAUAGACUGUUGGUAAGGUAAAUUGGGUUUUCAAUGUCAGGAACAAAUAAAAUUUUGCAAAUAGAAGUCAUCAAAUAAUUCAACAGGAAGACCAUACUGGACACAGAUGUUGUCAGUUACUUCUGGACAAUGUGGUAACAUGGAUAUUUCAGUCACUGGUAACAAUGUCAGGGUUAACACCCAAUGAAUUAUUUGAAACAAUUUGGGUUGCAAAAUUUGAAAUUAAUUAGUCUAUUUUGAGAUUGAUUUUCUACGUGGGCCAAUUUUAUGUCCAUUACCUAAAGCCACAAUCUCCCGCUCUAAGGAGUUAAAGGAUGAAAACACCCAACUGCUACACUGGAAUGGCAGACUGGAUAUUCAAGCAUUUUGGCAUUUAAUGCCUGCUAAAUUUUUGUCCGAUUAUAUAUAGAUUUGAUGUAUAUUAUUACCCAGUAAAUUCUUCUUGGGAAUUUUGUAUACAUUAUGGAAUAUUAGGAUAAGUUUUUGUAGGUCAGAAGAAUUUCAAGUAGUUUUUAGACAAAACAUAUCCAUGAGUGUGAAAAAAGCUGUGUUGACGAAUAGAUUACAUUUCACAUUUACCAGCAAGUCAGUAAAAAAUAGUGCUUAUUUACAUAGUCAAUAUAAUUUAAUGUUCUAAAAAUAAUAUCUUCGAUCUGCCCAAUAUUUAAUGUAUCAUUUGAGAUUUUUAAAAAUGCAUCCGCUCCAUUAUGUAAACAUUAAGAUAUGCCUAUGUUUCUUUAACUAUACAGCCUCUUUACAAUAAAUUUCUUGAUUUUUGUGCACAGGAUAGUAUUGCAACCUGCUAUUUAGCCUUUGGUGCCUUAGAAUUAUUAUAAAUAUUUAACAAUAUGUACAUAAUGUAAAUACUGCCAAGAGAUCAGUAAGGCCAAAUAUUUUCUCUAUUCACUUUUUAUUGCUCUUGCUUUCUAUUGCUACUAAAGCCUCUUUUAUCCAGCUUUGUAAUAGUUCCAACAUUGUAGCGAAUGUAAAUGUUUACUUUCAAUAAAUCUGAACUUGUUCAACAA